AGCUUCCGCCCCAGCCAGGGAAGCGGCAGGGGAAAGCACCGGCUCCAGGCCAGCGUGGGCCGCUCUCUCGCUCGGUGCCCGCCGCCAUGUGGGCCGUCCUGAGGUUAGCCCUGCGGCCGUGUGCCCGCGCCUCUCCCGCCGGGCCGCGCGCCUAUCACGGGGACUCGGUGGCCUCGCUGGGCACCCAGCCGGACUUGGGCUCUGCCCUCUACCAGGAGAACUACAAGCAGAUGAAAGCACUAGUAAAUCAGCUCCAUGAACGAGUGGAGCAUAUAAAACUAGGAGGUGGUGAGAAAGCCCGAGCACUUCACAUAUCAAGAGGAAAACUAUUGCCCAGAGAAAGAAUUGACAAUCUCAUAGACCCAGGGUCUCCAUUUCUGGAAUUAUCCCAGUUUGCAGGUUACCAGUUAUAUGACAAUGAGGAGGUGCCAGGAGGUGGCAUUAUUACAGGCAUUGGAAGAGUAUCAGGAGUAGAAUGCAUGAUUAUUGCCAAUGAUGCCACCGUCAAAGGAGGUGCCUACUACCCAGUGACUGUGAAAAAACAAUUACGGGCCCAAGAAAUUGCCAUGCAAAACAGGCUCCCCUGCAUCUACUUAGUUGAUUCGGGAGGAGCAUACUUACCUCGACAAGCAGAUGUGUUUCCAGAUCGAGACCACUUUGGCCGUACAUUCUAUAAUCAGGCAAUUAUGUCUUCUAAAAAUAUUGCACAGCUCAGACUGCUUUCUUUUUUUUUUUUUGAGAUGGAGUCUUGCUCUGUUGCCCAGGCUGGAGUGCAGUGGUGCUACCUCGGCUCACUGCAAACUUUGCCUCCCGGGUUCACGCUAUUCUCCUGCCUCAGCCUCCUGAGUAGCUGGGACUACAGGCGCCCACCACCAUGCCCGGCUAAUUUUUUGUAUUUUUAGUAGAGACAGGGUUUCACCACAUUAGCCAGGAUGGUCUCGAUCUCCUGACCUCGUGAUCUGCCGACCUCGUGAUCCGCCCGCCUCGGCCUCCCAAAGUGCUGGGAUAACAGGCAUGAGCCACCGCGCCUGGUCAAAU